AUACCAGGAGUUUGUCAGGGAACUGUUUCCAAAGCCAUAAUGAAUAAUCAGGCUGUUAGUAAAAGAAGCCUCUCCAAGUUAUAGCAUUUUUUAAAAAUUCUAGUAGUGAAGAAAAUAAUUAAAAGCCCAUCUGGUUGAGAUAGUAAUUCAUUAAGGAAAAAGAGGAGGCAGAAGGCUGGGGAAUAAUCGAUCCUUUUCUUUCUUUAUUUCAUGUGUUUCAGUUAUUGUGAAAUGAUAGUGAUCAAAAUCUGGAUUCUGGAUUGUGCAGAAUGCAGGAAAAUCCUAGGAACAUUCUUGGCGUGUUCUAAUAGUGGCUUCCCAGAAACGAGUGUUUUCAGUGGGUGUGGCGUCAUUGAGCUGAUGUGCUUUUGCAAGGGGUCUCUUUAGAAGUGGUAGGGGCAGGGUCGAGAGAAGAAGGGGAUGCAGAAUCUGUACAUGAGGAAGGAGCCAGAGUCACUCAGGAAACUCCUCAUUCUUCCUGCGCUGGCUGUGGCACACCCACCGGUGGCACACCCCUCCCUCGGGUCCAGUUCAGCCCACAGACUCCUGGGAGGAGAGCCAGGGCCCCAGCCUCUCCUUUGAGGAGUGUUGCAGCCUUUCUGUGUGCCAGAUGCCUAGUGAAGAAAAGCUGAAACCCUGGAGCUUUGUGCAUGUUAAUGACCUUGGAAAUGACUGAGCUCACGGACCCUCAUCACACCAUGGGAGACUACAAAGUGGCCCACCCUCAGGACCCUCACCACCCAUCAGAGAAGCCUGUCAUUCACUGCCAUAAAUGUGGGGAGCCUUGCAAGGGUGAAGUGCUUCGGGUCCAGACCAAACAUUUCCACAUCAAGUGUUUCACCUGCAAAGUGUGUGGCUGUGACCUGGCACAAGGGGGCUUCUUCAUAAAGAACGGAGAGUAUCUCUGCACCCUGGACUACCAGCGGAUGUACGGGACACGCUGCCAUGGCUGUGGGGAGUUCGUGGAGGGCGAAGUGGUGACUGCUCUGGGCAAGACCUACCAUCCCAAUUGCUUUGCUUGUACUAUCUGCAAGCGCCCGUUUCCACCCGGAGACCGAGUCACAUUCAAUGGGAGAGACUGCCUUUGUCAACUCUGUGCACAGCCGAUGUCGUCCAGUCCGAAAGAAACCACCUUCUCCAGCAAUUGUGCCGGCUGCGGAAGAGAUAUCAAGAAUGGGCAGGCGCUGCUGGCGCUGGAUAAGCAGUGGCACUUGGGGUGCUUUAAAUGCAAGUCCUGCGGGAAGGUCCUCACCGGGGAGUACAUCAGCAAGGAUGGUGCUCCGUACUGUGAAAAGGACUACCAGGGACUCUUUGGGGUGAAAUGUGAGGCGUGUCACCAGUUUAUCACAGGGAAAGUCCUGGAGGCAGGUGACAAACAUUACCACCCCAGCUGUGCACGAUGCAGCAGAUGCAACCAGAUGUUCACAGAAGGAGAGGAAAUGUAUCUUCAAGGCUCCACCGUUUGGCAUCCCGACUGUAAGCAAUCUACGAAGACCGAGGAAAAGCUGCGGCUGCCAAACAUUCGGCGUUCUUCAUCCGAUUUCUUUUAUUCCAAAAGUCUGAUUCGACGCACAGGACGGUCUCCGUCUCUGCAGCCUACCAGGACAUCCUCGGAAAGUAUUUAUUCUAGGCCAGGCUCCAGUAUUCCUGGCUCACCAGGUCAUACUAUCUAUGCAAAAGUAGACAAUGAGAUCCUGGAUUACAAGGAUUUAGCAGCCAUUCCGAAGGUCAAGGCAAUUUAUGACAUUGAACGUCCAGAUCUUAUUACCUAUGAGCCUUUCUACACUUCGGGCUAUGAUGACAAACAGGAGAGACAGAGCCUUGGAGAGUCUCCGAGGACUUUGUCUCCUACUCCAUCAGCAGAAGGGUACCAGGAUGUUCGGGAUCGGAUGAUCCAUCGGUCCACGAGCCAGGGCUCCAUCAACUCCCCUGUGUACAGCCGCCACAGCUACACUCCAACCACGUCCCGCUCUCCCCAGCAUUUCCACAGACCUGAGCUUUUGUCUCCUGGUGUGCAGAGGUUGUCGUACCUGCGCACCAGCAGCCUCAGCCCCACCCACAGCGACUCCCGCCCCAACCCCCCUUUCCGACACCACUUCAUUCCCCAUAUCAAAGGCAAUGAGCCGUCCAGCGGCCGGAACUCCCCUCUCCCUUACCGGCCAGACAGCCGCCCUCUAACUCCAACUUACGCUCAGGCCCCUAAACAUUUCCAUGUUCCAGAUCAAGGAAUCAACAUUUACCGAAAGCCACCCAUCUACAAACAGCAUGAUGCAGCUGCCUUGGCAGCCCAGAGCAAGUCCUCAGAAGAUAUCAUCAAGUUUUCCAAGUUCCCAGCAGCCCAGGCACCAGACCCCAGCGAGACACCAAAGAUUGAGACGGACCACUGGCCUGGUCCCCCCUCAUUUGCUGUCGUAGGACCUGACAUGAAACGCAGAUCUAGUGGCAGAGAGGAAGAUGAUGAGGAACUUCUGAGACGUCGGCAGCUUCAAGAAGAGCAAUUAAUGAAGCUUAACUCAGGCCUGGGACAGUUGAUCUUGAAAGAAGAGAUGGAGAAAGAGAGCCGGGAAAGGUCAUCUCUGUUAGCCAGUCGCUACGAUUCUCCCAUCAACUCAGCUUCACAUAUUCCAUCAUCUAAAACUGCAUCUCUCCCUGGCUAUGGAAGAAAUGGGCUUCACCGGCCUGUUUCUACCGACUUCGCUCAGUAUAACAGCUAUGGGGAUGUCAGCGGGGGAGUGCGAGAUUACCAGACACUCCCAGAUGGCCACAUGCCUGCAAUGAGAAUGGACCGAGGAGUGUCUAUGCCCAACAUGUUGGAACCAAAGAUAUUUCCAUAUGAAAUGCUCAUGGUGACCAACAGAGGGCGAAACAAAAUCCUCAGAGAGGUGGACAGAACCAGGCUGGAGCGCCACUUAGCCCCUGAAGUGUUUCGGGAAAUCUUUGGAAUGUCCAUACAGGAGUUUGACAGGUUACCUCUUUGGAGACGCAACGACAUGAAGAAAAAAGCAAAACUCUUCUAAGUCCCACUCGUGAAUGGCAAUUAGAGAAAGGACUGACAGUGGCGGUGCCCCAUAGGAUGUCAUAUUGAGGCCCAAACUUGAUUGGAGAAUUUGCAAACUACCGUCGCUCAGCAACACCAAAAAGAGAAAGUCUGGUUAAAACACCAUGAGUCAAAUGUCGGGCCAGCCAACAGUAACACUUGCCAAGAAGCAUGGCGUAGAAAUUUCUAUGUUCCGAAACACAGAGUAGUGUCCACAUGUGAGCUUUUCACAUUACCUUAUGUAUACAACAGGAGCUGCGUUGUUUUCUUCUUUUUCUUUUCCUUUAUCUGUUGUCCAACAACAGUGCUGACUGUCCGGAUAAGAGCUGGCAAGUGCCCUUAGGAUGCCGCAUGGGAAAAAUCGGUUAUCAUAAUUUCAAAGUAUAAAUAUAUUUAUUAAGUAGCGCUGCGGCUAAGAAGGAAGAGUGAGGGGUCUGUCCAUGGGGUGGCAGUGAUUUCACACCCGCCUUUCUUGAAUGGCUUCGUGUUACUCAGCCGUGCCCUGGCAGGAAUGGAACUCCAUCAGGGAACAGGGCAGCUCUGUUUGAAUGGGGUGAAAAACAGCAAAAUUAAUUCUUAGCAAGCUCCUUGUUCUCUACUGUUCACCGGGACCUGGCUGGCAAAUGACUUAGCUAUUAGUAUAUUUAAAAACUGUUCAAAAGCAAAAGAGAAGGAACAGGAAUGAAAGGAAACCUUCCCUUAACUCUUUCUGCUUCCCAUAGCAGGUCUGGUUCCUGCUCCCCGCCUAGGACAGGAGCUGUCUGGAGCUCCACCUUUGCAAAGAAAGGAAAAACACAAAUUGCCCCCAGAUUGGCCCAGUGGCAUGCCAUUAGGUGAUUUUGCAUAGGGGCCAUAUCAUUCAUGGCCAAAAAAAACCAAAAAGCAAAAAACAAAAACAAGUCCCAUGUCCUACUGACUCUAGUUCUUCCAGUCGUUAUCCUCUGCUGUCUCUCUGGCAUCCUAUGAAUCAGAUCAAGCCCAUGCUGUUGUUGGUUUUUAAGGUUUCUUUCAAUAAUAGGCUAAGGAAAGACAUGUUUUUCUCUUUUAAAUCUCUGCAACUCCAAAGUAGACUCCUUCGAACGUAUUUAAUUUGGCCUUUUCAGCUUUCUUCUUGCCCAGCUCUGUCGAAUUCAUGGGUGUGUGUGCACAUGUUGGUUUCACUCACCCAGAGUAAUUUUGUGAGCAUGCAUGUGCUUUUUAAUUUCUGCUUGAAUGUUUGUCCUGCUGUGUUGCAGCUUCUAAAGACAUUGUCACCGAGUGUGUGUGACUCAAAGAUCAAGAGUGAGGCUAAACUGCGACCCCAACAUCACUUCCUUCAUGGAAAGGUGUUGGCGCUGAUGUAGCUCAUGGAAGGAUCAGACUGGGAACCACAGAGGAAGGAUGAGGUGGGAUGUGGAGGUCAGAGCAUCUCACGAGAGUCCCUCAGGCUCUGCAACACUAGAUUCGAAUAUGAGCCUAGGGUUUCCCCAACACGUGCGUGCAUAUGAAACCACAUCAUGAUUCCCGACGUGAGUUAGAUGAGGGAGAGUUUGUGUAACUCCACACCCAGGAGGGUAAGCCACUUUAUUAUCAUGCUUUGGGGCUGUGCUUAAGAAUUUAAGCUCUGUUUUAAAGCCGAAGAAGAAAACAUUUGAAUUUACCUUCAUAUGCCACUAAGAACAAAAGCUCUGAAGUUCUUCCUGCUGGCACCAAAUAUUAGGAUUACAAGCUGUCUCUCUGACACCAGUGGUAAAAAAGCAAGUAGAAUAGUUUCUGAGUCUGUGUUGCAGCCUCUGACACGUGGCUCACCGCUGUCAUUUGGGGGAUGGAAUGAACAGUCACUGUUCUAUAGCAUCCUCCUGUGCUCUUACCUAAGGAAUCUAAAUUGUCCUAGCCUUCCAUUGCUAUGCACUGAAUGAGGACUACUCUCGUGUGUGUGUGUGUGUGUGUGUGUGUGUGUGUGUGUGUGUGUGUGUGUGUUGGAUCUACUAACAUGUUUAGCAAAUGGCUCUGACAGGGUGGCCAUGAGCAGAUGAGACCAGCUCUUGCUUGGUUGGAAGCCACACUGCAGUUUGCAGUUUAGCCUUUGGUGUCUCAGUGGCUUCUUGCUUAUUCCAUGCUUUUUCUAUCCCAUCCUCUCUCUGUGCCCUCCUGCAAUGGCAGCCUUGGCACAAUGCCUGGGUGUCCUCAUCCUUGCUUUACUCUGGAAAGUGUGGGGAUGGAGAGGAUGGUGCAUUUCCAGUGCUUCCUUACCUGUCAAUAACAAUGGUGGCCACCUGGGUCCCAGCACUUGGCUGGUGGAGAGAUUUUUUUCAUUAUGGAGCUAAUAAAGGGUCCCUACGUUUUACAUUGAUUAAUGAAUUAUCACCCAGACAUGUGCAGAUGAAAUGUCAAUAUAAGAAAAAUCAAGGUAUUUGGGAAACAUGGGCAUAAUCAGGUAGUUUUGCUAAAAUUCCUCUUCCUUGGUCUACAUAAAGAAGACAUGGGUCUGUCAUAGAAUGGGGACAUUAGACUGAAAACUGGGACAACCCCCUUCCUUAUUUUAUAGAGACUAGGAGUUAAGGGGCCUGCCUAAGAUUGCAGUGAUAAAGAACUGAACCCUAAAUCAGCUCCCACUAAUGAAACCCUGCUUUCCUUGUAUCUUUUAAACUCAGUUCUGCAUCCAACUUGAGAAGAAAAAAAGCUUCUUUCCAUAUCAAGUACCAUAUGAGUUCAUUUAAACUGCACCUUGCAGAAAUGCAUUGCCAGAAAGCACCAGUAGCCUCCUAUCUGCAAGCAGAGUAGUGCUCUGCUCUGGGGAGGGGUCAUUGGAAACCAUAAUGCAGAGUGGGCCCCCUACUCCAUUUCCCAGCAAAAGGCUCCAGCUGGAGGGAUGGGUUGUGGGGCAACCUGGUUCCUGCUAACUGCCAGAUUGAAUGUGUGGGCUAGAAUGCCUGCACAUUUAGUUAAACUGGGCUCAGCAUGCUUGUCCUCAAAAUGUCCAUCCUGGUCACAGCACACAAGAUGGCUAUUGGUCUGCUUUUACCCUACCCUGUACUAUACAUGAAAAUUCCAGUUAUUAACACACUCAAACUGGUGGAGCUUGUUCACCCUAGGAAGGGGAUUGUAUAUAUGGCAGGCUUCCCUGGUGCCGAUGUAAAGGGCUACAUUUGGGAACAUUUGACUUCCUUGGGACUCUUAAGUGCAUAAUGAUGGCAUGAAGUAAAAGGGGCCUCAAUGAUGAUAGGAAAAUCAGUUCUUUUAAAAUUUCUUCAAGAAAAUCCAGGCUAUCACAUAGUCUUUCUGUGUGACUUAUUAGGAGAUAGGAAGAGCAUUGGGAAACUUGCACAGCUAGCUAUGCAUCUACAUUUUGGUUUGGGGUUAGUUAUGAAAUGUUCUUAAUAUGACGUGUUCAAUAACUUCACAUAAACUUCCUGUUCUCCAAAACCUCAAAGAGAUAGAGUUAAUGAGUUGUUGUUUUUUUUUAAAUGGGGGUAGUUUUCUAUCUGUCAUGGGCUCUAGCAUCUACUCCGCUACCCAAUUCUGUCAUCUCCAAGCUGAGUUUCCUCUUCUGAGGCAGAGGCUGGAGCAGUUCUUUUUCAGUUCUCAUCCUCUCCAUCCCAAUCCAGUAUAUCAAUCAACUCUAACUCGGAGACGUCUAGCUGGCAAUGUUUCUAAAACUUUCACUGGAUUUCUUUAGACAUUGAAGCAAACAUUUUUUUCUAAGAAUUGCUUCUCAGAUGAUGAUAUCAAAUGUAUAUGCUUUUGCAAGUUUGAAAAGUUCAAAUUAACCACUUUUGACUAGGUAAGUCUUUCUAAAAACCAUUUAAAGCUAACUGGGUCUUAGCAUCCUCCUGUGUAUGGAAGAGACAGGUGACCGCUCCAGGUUGGGUGCUCACAGAACCCUUUUCCUGACUCUCAUGGAAGAUGGUGGAAGGAAAAUAGACUGUCUCAUCAACCCUCCUGUGUCCUCUGAAGCAAUCUCAGUUUUUAUUAACCACCUCUUCUGUGUUUCUGGUAGCUAUUUAACCUGUAUUUAAUCUGUACUUCCUAUGCCAGCCUCAAUUUUAUUUGAUUUUUACAAUUAUUCUCUUCUAACCAAUGAAGUGUUUGUCAGUAUGCCCCAAAGCUUGCUCUUUUGUGCUCCCUUUUGAAUAACUUUCUAUCCAGAAAAAGAGAUUAUUUGGGACUUGAGAUUUGCAGUGAUACCAACUUAUAGCAAUGAUGUACUUUAAGGGAACUACCCAACUAUGUUGUGAUAGAAGAAAGAGAAACCUUCACUUUGGCAUUUUUUUUUAAUCACUGUUUAUUUUUCUGUUUGCGGCCCAGGAAGCAGUGGGAGGUGGUGGCAGAUAUGCUUUGCAUAUGGAUUGUUAUGUUUUUAUUUGGGCAAGUUUAAUCAUGGAAAACUCAAAAAGAAGGGGGGAAAUGGUCAGUUUAAGCCAAAAGAAACUUUCUAAACAAUGUAUAGGUACACAGCAAAAUUAAACAAAUCCAACAAUUUCUGAAGCUUAGUGUAAUUGAGUGGUGGUUGUUAUUCAAUAAAAUUAUUCCCAAAAGUGUUUCUCCUAAGAGUGCAGUUCCCAUGAGUCACUUCCUGAACCCAUUGACCAAAGGUGGACAGAGACAAUCCUGUAGACCUUGACAUUCAGAAAGAUGUGAGCUGCUUACUGAUCAUAUAUGCAUACGUUUCUUUACAGCAGAGGAAACCAUUGUCCACAAAACUGAUGUUCUUUUGGGGUUUUAUGUACAGACUUGUCCAAUCAUGUGUGUGGUUCCUGCGAGUUGCUGAUGACUCCGCAUUGAAGCUCUCUGAGUUCUUUGAUUUUAAGUUGGGUUUAUGGAAUUUUUUCAAAUGUUGGAAGGUGUGUGGUUCUUCCUGCCCUCCCUCCCCUUUUGGAAAUAUGAAAGCAAAUGUUUAGAAGAAUUCCUUUUGAAAAGCUGUGUCGUGUUCCCUGUGAAACUGAGCAGGUGUGUGUUGGCGCGCUAAGUGCCACAUGCUUGUGUGUAGAGGAGGAGGUGGCCCUGCCGGCUCCGCGCUGCUGUGCCUGUGAUCCCUACCUGCUCCCCGCUCCUGUUGCCAGCAGCACUCACUGCACUCCUUUGUCAUAUACUCUGCAUCACUGUCAUACUCACAACUUCGUGAAUAAAGUUGUGUGCUUUAUUCGUAGA